CUGUUUCUCAGCUUCCCGGCCCAGCUGGGGCACCCACUGGAAGGAGAGGCCAGGCGGAAGACCCUGGCUCCGUCAUGGCCUCUGCCCUGAGGCCACCCCGUGUCCCCAAGCCUAAGGGUGUCCUGCCUUCACACUACUAUGAGAGCUUUCUAGAGAAGAAGGGGCCCUGUGACCGGGAUUACAAGAAGUUCUGGGCAGGCCUGCAGGGUCUCACCAUUUAUUUCUACAAUAGCAAUCGGGACUUCCAGCACGUGGAGAAGCUCAACUUGGGAGCAUUUGAGAAACUCACAGAUGAGAUUCCCUGGGGAAGCUCACGUGACCCUGGCACCCACUUCAGCCUGAUUCUCCGGGAUCAGGAGAUCAAGUUCAAGGUAGAGACCUUGGAGUGUCGGGAAAUGUGGAAAGGCUUCAUCUUAACGGUGGUGGAGCUCCGUGUCCCGACCGACUUGACCCUGCUUCCUGGGCACCUAUACAUGAUGUCUGAAGUCUUGGCCAAAGAGGAGGCGCGCCGUGCACUGGAGACACCCUCGUGCUUCCUGAAGGUGAGCCGGCUGGAGGCACAACUGCUCCUGGAGCGCUACCCCGAGUGCGGGAACCUGCUGCUGCGGCCCAGCGGGGACGGCGCCGACGGCGUGUCGGUCACCACGCGGCAGAUGCACAACGGGACGCACGUGGUCCGGCAUUACAAGGUGAAGCGGGAGGGCCCCAAGUACGUGAUCGAUGUGGAACAGCCGUUCUCUUGCACCUCCCUGGACGCCGUGGUCAACUAUUUCGUGUCGCAUACCAAAAAGGCGCUGGUGCCAUUCCUGUUAGACGAGGACUACGAGAAGGUGCUAGGCUACGUGGAAGCCGAUAAGGAGAAUGGCGAGAAUGUGUGGGUGGCGCCCUCCGCUCCGGGCCCAGGUCCUGCACCCUGCACAGGUGGCCCCAAGCCGCUGUCACCUGCGUCUAGCCAGGACAAGCUGCCCCCACUGCCCCCACUACCGAACCAGGAAGAGAACUACGUGACCCCCAUUGGAGAUGGCCCAGCUGUUGACUAUGAGAACCAAGAUGUGGCUUCCUCUAGUUGGCCAGUCAUCCUGAAGCCAAAGAAGUUGCCAAAGCCUCCUGCCAAGCUUCCAAAGCCACCCGUUGGACCCAAGCCAGUAGAGAAGGGGUUUCACCAUGUUGCCCAGGCUGGUCUCGAACUCCUGACCUCAAGUGAUCCACCCACCUCAGCCUCCCAAAGUGCUGGGAUUACCGGCGUGAGCCACCACACCUGGCCUCAUCUGUCUUCUCUUCCAGAGCCCAAAGUCUUUAAUGGUGGCUUGGGCAGGAAGCUGCCAGUCAGUUCAGCCCAGCCUCUCUUCCCCACAGCCGGGCUGGCAGACAUGACGGCAGAGCUACAGAAGAAGCUGGAGAAGAGGCGGGCACUGGAGCACUGAUUCGGACACACCAGGGACCAGCGGGCUAGUCCCAGGGCAUGGCCCAGCGGCCAGAUUCUUUUUCCCAGGAUUAAAACUCUGACCCCAGGA